GUUUAUCAUUUUAAUGAGAGUAGAAUAAUAAACAGUCUGAAAUUUUAAGGAGUUACAUAAAAAGCAAUAUAGCCUUUUCCUCUUUCGCUUGCUGUCUCCCCUUCCCCUCCUUCUUUCUCCAAAUGGAGGGAGUUCUUUUUUUCUUCUUCCAUCUCAUCUACUCAAUAACGGAGCCGCUGCAGCCGCUGCACGCUGCACACACACGGCACAGUCCCUGGGUCCGGGAGCCAGAGCAGCGCCACUCGGAGACGGGAUGGUUCCGUGGGUUGUGUAGGAGCACAGGAAAGCGGAGGCCGGGCCACACAGCACCGCGAACCCAGCAGCCCAAGCCCAGCGGACCAAGCAGCCACCCCCGGGAGCCGCCACUGCCUGGAGCAGUCACCGGCGGGAGCCUCCAUUUCCAGGAGCCGCCACCGCUGGGAGCUGCCACAGCCGGGAGCCGCCACCGCCAGAAGCCUCCAUCUCCCGGGAGCCGCCAUCGCUGGGAGCCGCCACCUCCAGGAGCCGCCACGGCCACCGGGAGCCGUCACCGCAGGGAACCUCCAUCUCCUGGAGCCACCACCGCUGGGAGCUGCCACCUCAGGAGCAGCGGCAGCACUGGGACCCGCCGGGCCCCCUCGCACCCAGCGGCUCUGCAGGUGCCCUACACCCGGGAGGGGCCGAGGGAGCCCACGCCGCCGGCGGGACCGCAGGGAUUUGCUGGCUCUUUCUGCGCUGAGGGGUCGCGGCGCGGGGCGGAGGUCGGGUGGGGAAAGCUGGAGCCGCAGGGAACGCGCAGGACAGGCUCGCUGGGUGUCGACUCUAGCCCUCUGUCAGAGACCUUGGGACCCGCGCAAUGUGGCAGUGGAAGGCGCAGGGUCUGACCCCGGCCGCGGCCGCCGCAGCAGCUGAUCUGUCAACCCCGGCCAGAGCCGAGCCGCCUGAGGCCUGCAGUGUUCUCCAUCACCACUGUGAUGGCAUCCGCUUCCGUGACUGUCACUGUGCACCCUCCGCCUGUCCUGGGCCCACGCAGGACCCCCAAGCGGGGCUCUGCACAGGCCAGGAGGGCUACCCAGGGACUGACCACGGGUUGUUCAUGGGUCCUCACCUGCUUUUCCAGGUCCAGGGUGAGAGGACGAAUUUGAAGGUAGAAGUCACAGAGUUGCAGGAUGUGGAGUGCGAGGAGUGGCCCCGGGGAAGCAGCUCCAACUGAGGGUGAUUAAAAUCUGAAGCAGGCCGGGCGCAGUGGCUCACAUCUGUAAUCCCAGCACUUUUGGAGGCCGAGGCAGGUGGAUCACCUGACGUCAGGAGUUCGAGACCAGCCUGGGCAACAUGGUGAAACCCCGUCUCUGCUAAAAAUACAAAGUUAGCCAGGCAUGAUGGCGAGCGCCUGUAAUCCCAGCUACUAGGGAGGCUGAGGCACGAGAAUCGCUUGAACCUGGGAGGGGGAGGUUGCAGUCACCUGAGAUUGGACCAUUGCACUCCAGCCUGGGCAACAAGAGCGAAACUCCAUCUCAGAAAAAAAAAAAAAAAAAAAAAAUCUAAAGUAAAGAGGUCAAAGAUCGGAAACCCCUGCCCCUACACCUUUCAAGAACUGCUUGUGUCUGUAACCCUUAGCAGGCUCUGACCUAGUCAGGCUAGAAGAAGCAUAAGGAUCUUUUAUUGCUUUGUGCUGGGUGAGGGCUGGCCCUAAACAUCUGCCUAAUCCUUUCAACGGGCCCAGGAAAAGCCAGACUGGCAUCAUGUCCACAGCAUCGCUUAAUAUCGUUGGUUGUCAUCCAGACACCUCAACUUGUGCUGCAGAGGAAAUAAGUUCCUUCUCACGGAUCAUCAUGAUGGAUAUUGAAACCUCAGGGUGCAGAACUAACACCUGUUCAUCAUCGUGGAUGUUAAAGAAUUGGGUAACAUGCCAAGCGGUAAGCCUUGGAUGGGCCAUGAGAAUAUCCUCUAAAAAGCACGCAGUAUUGUGCCCCUCUCACAACCAACACACACAUGACCUGUCCCCUGGCACCCCCAAAUUUAAGAGUGGAUUGCAAAUCUUUUGGAGACCAUGGCCCUGCUACAUGUAGAAAAACCUGUUCUGCUAUUCCUGGGCCCACAAUAAACCCAGAAAUUAUGUUUUGAGUUACUGUGAUUUAAACUCCCUCUCUUCUUAAAUGGAACAGCUCAUUGGGGCUUUCUGGAUCUGUUUCCAUUUUUCUUUAAAAAUAAAUUGUGAGCAUGCAUUGUGGUGAUGCAGAGGCAGGCAUUCUGUGAGAUACAAGCUCCAGAAGGAUUCUCCUCAAUGUGUCAGUGUUGGGAUGCACACUUCCUAAAUAAAUCAUCAUUGUCUCCGUCUUCUCCAUUAAUAGCGCUCUUUCAGUGUGACAUGGAAAAGCAGGAUGGCAUACACCCCACUGAAGGAUGUAGGCGGAGGCAGAUCUCUCAACCAGGCAUAUUGCUUCUGUACUGCUCUUCUUUUGCUCUAAGGUAUGGGUUCCCUCAACCUCUUAGCUAGAGACCAGCAAAUGUCAGGGAAGCACCCGGUGUCUGGCUCCCCUUCCAAAUCAACACCAGUGUCUUGUUACAGACAAGAAGUCAGAGGAAAGGGCGGGGUCCCAGCAGGGCAGAAGCCUAAGCUACUAUGAGGCACUCACAAGUGGCAGCUCCUGUUACUCCCUCUUAAAUUAUGUGGGAAAUCUUAACGGAAGGGCAAUGGGCCCCAGGAAUACCUGCAGCGUAGUGACCUCAGAUCCUGAUACUCACCAUGAAACUCUAAGAUACUGAUUGGAAGCGACUUGUGGCUGCUGGCUGUGUGUGUGACUCUGCCGGGGACCCUGGCAGCCCCCCUGUAGCUGUCUUGAUGCCUCUCUGUCACCCACAUCAUCUGCCUACUUAACGCCCAGCUCUGCUCAGAAAACGUUAUGUCCUGUGUCGAGGAGAGACGACGCAAAAUUCUGAAGUCCAUUUCCCUCUGGCUCCUGGCAUACCCUCGCUCCUUUUCUGAGCCCAGCUCGUGGUGUGCCAGAGCCUGUGUGGUCCCCUGACUUCUGCACAGUGUAGAACUUUCUCCAAUAGUCACAAUGGCAAAGGGAGAACUGGGGGGCUGGCAGGUAAUUAGAAUUUCUCUCCCUCUCUCUUUUAAUACUUUCAUUUUGAAUGUCUUAUUUGUUCAUGUGUAUGUUUUAACUUAAAAAAUUCUUUCUGAUAUUUUUAAUUUUGUGUCAUAAGAAUGUUUUCCUCUACAGUAUUUGUCAUACCAGUUUAUAACCACAGAAAUGCAGAGAUUUUAUUUCUAUUGGAAACAUUACUACAGCUAUGUUUUACUUUUGAACAGAAUUUUUACUUGUAUAGGGUGCUUACUAAUGUUAAAUAGUUUGGAGUAUAUAACAUUUACAUUAAGGACUCAUGGUAGGUUAAAACCCUAAAGGGUAAGGGGUUUAAAGGAAAUAAAUAUUCAAACUGAGUCUUAUUGCCAAUUUUGGUGUAAAUGAGUUUGUGUCAUUUCAAUUACAAAGAUAAAAGUAUGCCAUAUAAUUUAUGUAAAAUUUGUUUUUGUGGUGUACAUAAUAGUUAUCAAGUCUGUUGACAGAAGUAUAUUUUAAAAGAAUAUACAUGUGAUGAAUCCAUAAUAUCUGAAACUUUGCUGAGAUAUGAGUGGGGCACACUUCAUUGUAAAUUACAGCAAGGAAAGAAAUUAAGGAAAGAAGUUAAGAGAGUGAGAGUGAGUGGAUAUUCACACAAUUGUGAAAUGUUUAUUAGUUACCUUUUGUGAUGUAGUGUGGUUCUCAUUUUAAACCUUGGAAGGUGAAAAUGUACAAACUAUAAAUAUGAAUGUUCAAACACUGACAGAAAUUCUAAUAUGAAUUAAAAAAUAACGAAAAAACAACAAUAUAUUUUAUCUUACUAAUUAUGAACUUGGUUAUUCUAUUAUUCAUUCUAAUGAAUAUUUUAAGUGAUGGUUUAAUUUUAUUCACAUAUAGUUGCCAUUAAAAGGUUAACUCUCUCAUAAAAACAUUUUUUCUAUUUUAA